GGAGCGCGUGAGGACCCGCGCGUCGCCGGGGACACUGAGCGAGGGUAGCGGCCAGGUCACCGGCUGAGGACACUGCUCCUGAAGCCCGGUCAGGCGGUCGCGCCCUCCCUGGCGGCCCCCGCGGCCCCGCAGGACCUGUGCCCCGACGUCGCCGACCCGCGGUCCCCGCUGUCGCCGACCCGCGGCGUCCGUCGGGCGAGUGGGCCUGCCCGCGGGUAAGGCGCCGGCCCUGGGCCGCCCUCCCGGGAAUCGGGAGCCGCCGCUGCAGCUUCGUAGAUCAGAAGUCGGUUGUCGGUCUCACUGGACUACAAUCAAGGUGCCAGCAGGACUGUGUUCGUUUCUGGAAAUUCUAGAAGAUGAUCUGUUUCCUUGCCUCUUCUAGCUCCUAGAGGUCACUCACAUCAUUCUUCGGCCGUGGCCCCUUCCUCCACCUUCAAAGCCCACAACAUUGCAUCUCUCCGACCUUCUUCCAUAGUCAUAUUUUCCUCUGACUGUGGCUAGGAGGGUCCUCUGAUUGUUAAGACUCAUGUAAUUAGAUUGGGCUCACCAGGAUCGUCCAGGAUAAUCUUCCAAUCUCAAGUGUGGUUUAUUGACAAUCAUUUACAAUGCCGAAGAGUGCUGUAGUGAGCCAGCACAGUGGGUAACACAGCAACGGAGAACAGAUGCAGGUUUGAGGAAUUUAACUUGCUAAAACCUUGAACUGAAGUCUUAGAGAUUGGAACAUACGGGUUUGUAUAAAUAGGCUUUUAAGCCCUGUUUGCAAUGGGUUACUGAUAGGAGAAACUUGCUUGUGGAAUGUCAGCUGCGUGAGCUCACUGUCAGACAAGAUGGAAGAAGAAGGGCUGGAGUGUCCAAACUCUUCCUCUGAAAAACGCUAUUUUCCUGAAUCCCUGGAUUCCAGCGAUGGGGAUGAGGAAGAGGUUUUGGCCUGUGAGGAUUUGGAACUUAACCCCUUUGAUGGAUUGCCAUAUUCAUCACGUUAUUAUAAACUUCUGAAAGAAAGAGAAGAUCUUCCUAUAUGGAAAGAAAAAUACUCCUUUAUGGAGAACCUGCUUCAAAAUCAAAUCGUGAUUGUUUCAGGAGAUGCUAAAUGUGGUAAGAGCGCUCAGGUUCCUCAGUGGUGUGCUGAAUAUUGUCUUUCCAUCCACUACCAGCACGGGGGCGUGAUAUGCACACAGGUCCACAAGCAGACUGUGGUCCAGCUCGCCCUGCGGGUGGCGGAUGAAAUGGAUGUUAACAUUGGUCAUGAGGUUGGCUACGUGAUCCCUUUCGAGAACUGCUGUACCAACGAAACAAUCCUGAGGUAUUGUACUGAUGAUAUGCUGCAAAGAGAAAUGAUGUCCAAUCCUUUUUUGGGUAGCUAUGGGGUCAUCAUCUUAGAUGAUAUUCAUGAAAGAAGCAUUGCAACUGAUGUGUUACUUGGACUUCUUAAAGAUGUUUUACUAGCAAGACCAGAACUGAAGCUCAUAAUUAACUCCUCACCUCACCUGAUCAGCAAACUCAAUUCUUAUUAUGGAAACGUGCCUGUCAUAGAAGUGAAAAAUAAACACCCUGUGGAGGUUGUGUACCUUAGUGAGGCUCAAAAGGAUUCUUUUGAGUCUAUUUUACGCCUUAUCUUUGAAAUUCACCACUCGGGUGAGAAAGGUGACAUUGUAGUCUUUCUGGCCUGUGAACAAGAUAUUGAGAAAGUCUGUGAAACUGUCUAUCAAGGAUCUAACCUAAACCCAGAUCUUGGAGAACUGGUGGUUGUUCCUUUGUAUCCAAAAGAGAAAUGUUCAUUGUUCAAGCCACUCGAUGAAACAGAAAAAAGAUGCCAAGUUUAUCAAAGAAGAGUGGUGUUAACUACUAGCUCUGGAGAGUUUUUGAUCUGGAGCAACUCAGUCAGAUUUGUUAUCGAUGUGGGUGUGGAAAGAAGAAAGGUGUACAACCCGAGAAUAAGAGCAAACUCGCUCGUCAUGCAGCCCAUCAGCCAGAGCCAGGCAGAGAUACGCAAGCAGAUUCUUGGCUCAUCUUCUUCAGGAAAAUUUUUCUGCCUGUACACUGAAGAAUUUGCCUCCAAAGACAUGACGCCACUGAAGCCAGCAGAAAUGCAGGAAGCCAACCUAACAAGCAUGGUGCUUUUUAUGAAGAGGAUAGACAUUGCGGGCCUAGGCCACUGUGACUUCAUGAACAGACCAGGUAGCCUUAUGCUCCCAUGUCAGCCAGGCAUUAGGCUGAGAUUCACCUUCUCCUGCCCAUUCUCUGUCCUGAGUUCACAUGAUGCGCAGCAAUGCACACAAGCAUGGAGGGGGCGUUGGUUUGGACUGAAGCAUUUUCCUGCUAGAGCACCAGAAAGUUUGAUGCAGGCAUUGGAAGACUUAGAUUAUCUGGCAGCACUGGAUAAUGAUGGAAAUCUUUCUGAAUUUGGAAUCAUCAUGUCAGAGUUUCCUCUUGAUCCACAACUCUCGAAGUCUAUCUUAGCGUCCUGUGAAUUUGACUGUGUAGAUGAAGUGCUAACAAUCGCAGCCAUGGUAACAGCUCCAAAUUGCUUUUCACAUGUGCCACAUGGAGCUGAAGAGGCUGCCUUGACUUGUUGGAAGACAUUUUUACAUCCCGAAGGAGAUCACUUUACCCUCAUCAGCAUUUACAAGGCUUACCAAGACACAACUCUGAAUUCUAGCAGUGAGUACUGUGUGGAAAAGUGGUGUCGUGAUUACUUCCUCAACUGUUCAGCACUCAGAAUGGCAGAUGUUAUUCGAGCUGAACUCUUAGAAAUUAUCAAGCGAAUCGAGCUUCCCUAUGCAGAACCUGCUUUUGGCUCCAAGGAAAACACUCUAAACAUAAAGAAAGCUCUUCUGUCCGGUUACUUUAUGCAGAUUGCUCGGGAUGUUGAUGGAUCAGGUAACUACUUAAUGCUGACACAUAAGCAGGUUGCUCAGCUGCAUCCCCUGUCUGGUUACUCAAUCACCAAGAAGAUGCCAGAGUGGGUCCUCUUCCAUAAAUUCAGCAUUUCUGAGAACAACUACAUCAGGAUUACCUCAGAAAUCUCUCCUGAACUAUUUAUGCAGCUGGUACCACAAUACUAUUUCAGUAAUCUGCCUCCUAGUGAAAGUAAGGACAUUCUACAGCAAGUAGUGGAUCACCUAUCCCCUGUGUCAACAAUGAAUAAGGAACAGCAAAUGUGUGAGACGUGCCCUGAAACUGAACAGAGAUGCACUCUCCAGUGACUCCCCAGCAAACACAAGGUGCAGCAGGGUCCCAAAGGUAGCUGGAUGGCUGAACUGCUGGAUAUGGGAGAUACAUGACGCGAAGACGGAUUUCACAUCCACAGGACGGUCUUGAAGAAAAUAACACUGUGUAUAUUAUUUUAAAAUAAAAAAUAGAAGUUUUUAUUGAGUUCUUUAAAUUACUACUCCAUGCUUUUCUUCUUCUUGGAAAAGUUUUUAAAUCAACCACUCAUAAUUUGACCAAAAUUUUAAAAAACUGGUAUUUUGUAAAUGUGUCAGAGACACAUGGGACAGAACCCUACUUUUUGUAGAGGAACUUAAUCUGAAUAAAGUCUGAGUUUUUCAGUAAA